GUGUCAGCUGACCCAAGGGGCCUUCGAGGUGCCUUAGGCCGCUUGCCUUGCUCUCAGAAUCGCUGCCGCCAUGGCUAGUCAGUCUCAGGGGAUUCAGCAGCUGCUGCAGGCCGAGAAGCGGGCAGCCGAGAAGGUGUCCGAGGCCCGCAAAAGAAAGAACCGGAGGCUGAAGCAGGCCAAAGAAGAAGCUCAGGCUGAAAUUGAACAGUACCGCCUGCAGAGGGAGAAAGAAUUCAAGGCCAAGGAAGCUGCGGCAUUGGGAUCCCGUGGCAGUUGCAGCACUGAAGUGGAGAAGGAGACCCAGGAGAAGAUGACCAUCCUCCAGACAUACUUCCGGCAGAACAGGGAUGAAGUCUUGGACAACCUCUUGGCUUUUGUCUGUGACAUUCGGCCAGAAAUCCAUGAAAACUACCGCAUAAAUGGAUAGAAGAGAGAAGCACCUGUGCUGUGGAGUGGCAUUUUAGAUGCCCUCACGAAUAUGAAGCUUAGCACAGCUCUAGUUACAUUCUUAUGAUAUGGCAUUAAAUUAUUUCCAUAUAUUAUAUAAUAGGUCCUUCCACUUUUUGGAGAGUAGCAAAUCUAGCUUUUUUGUACAGACUUAGAAAUUAUCUAAAGAUUUCAUCUUUUUACCUCAUAUUUCUUAGGAAUUUAAUGGUUAUAUGUUGUCUUUUUUUCCUAUGUCUUUUGGCUCAAGCAACAUGUAUAUCAGUGUUGACUUUUUCUUUCUUAGAUCUAGUUUAAAAAAAAAAAAAACCACAUAACAAUUCUUUGAAGAAAGGAAGGGAUUAAAUAAUUUUUUUCCCUAACACUUUCUUGAAGGUCAGGGGCUUUAUCUAUGAAAAAGUAGUAAAUAGUUCUUUGUAACCUGUGUGAAGCAGCAGCCAGCCUUAAAGUAGUCCAUUCUUGCUAAUGGUUAGAACAGUGAAUACUAGUGGAAUUGUUUGGGCUGCUUUUAGUUUCUCUUAAUCAAAAUUACUAGAUGAUAGAAUUCAAGAACUUGUUACAUGUAUUACUUGGUGUAUCGAUAAUCAUUUAAAAGUAAAGACUCUGUCAUGCAUUUUUCCCCAUUCUUUUUUUUUUCCCUGUCUCCGUGACAACCAGUGGUUCUUCAUUUUUGAUCAUGCGAAAUGCAUUUUGACCCAGAUGGUCUGCAGAACUUCACUUAGGACAUUAGCACACAAAUAGCACACAUAUCACAUACCCAUUUAUAUACAUAAUUAGAAAAUGUUCCUGAUACAUGUGUCAUGUGAUUUCUUCCAACAAAUGUUUUGGAAAACAGCAAGCAACUAGUCUGUAGGUUGUCUUUUCUCUAGAGAUCCUUGUCCUGGGACAGCCUGGGGCAAGUUAUUAAGCAUAUUUCCUUCCUGGUGGGCUAGAUGAUGUGCAUUAUACCUGUAGUACCUUCAUACUAGCCCUUACAAGUUAAAUGUCCUGUGGCCAUCUUAGCCGAAAGUCUUUGGUUGCAAAAUCUUAUAGGUAAAAACAGUUGAAAGAACAUUAUGGGAUUUCCUUGCUUGUUCUGAUACAAUACAACUAGAUGACCUUAAAAACCCUCAUAUUUAA